GUGAGAUGCGAGCCGGCCAACAGCUUGCAAGCAUGCUCCGCUGGACCCGAGCCUGGAGGCUCCCGCGUGAGGGACUCGGCCCCCACGGCCCUAGCUUCGCGAGGGUGCCUGUCGCACCCAGCAGCAGCAGCGGCGGCCGAGGGGGCGCCGAGCCGAGGCCGCUUCCGCUUUCCUACAGGCUUCUGGACGGGGAGGCAGCCCUCCCGGCCGUCGUCUUUUUGCACGGGCUCUUCGGCAGCAAAACUAACUUCAACUCCAUCGCCAAGAUCUUGGCCCAGCAGACAGGCCGUAGGGGAUGACCGGGAGCUCACCACCUCUUAUGGCAGCCCAUUCUUCUGUGCUCCUACUGUUGGAAAUUCCUGGAGUCUCCUUCCUGGCAUUCUCCGAGAUUGCCACCCAGCCAGGCCAGCCCUUCAGAGACGUGGUCACAACCCUGGGGCCUGCUCUUCUCUGGCAGAGUGGCCCCAGGUUCUUCAUCUGGGCCUCCUAGGUCUGGAAACUGGGCCCUUCCCCUCCACAGGGUGUAUCCCCAGGCUCUCCACACCUUUGACCUGCUGUCCCUACAAGCCUUUGGCUGUCUACCCCCAGAAUGGGGAUAUCAACGCAGCCCCGUCUCACCCCACUCCCCAGGUGCUGACGGUGGAUGCUCGUAACCACGGUGACAGCCCCCACAGCCCAGACAUGAGCUACGAGAUCAUGAGCCAGGACCUGCAGGACCUUCUGCCCCAGCUGGGCCUGGUGCCCUGCGUCGUCGUUGGCCACAGCAUGGGAGGAAAGACAGCCAUGCUGCUGGCACUACAGAGGCCAGAGCUGGUGGAACGUCUCAUUGCUGUAGAUAUCAGCCCAGUGGAAAGCACAGGUGUCUCCCACUUUGCAACCUAUGUGGCAGCCAUGAGGGCCAUCAACAUCGCAGAUGAGCUGCCCCGCUCCCGUGCCCGAAAACUGGCGGAUGAACAGCUCAGUUCUGUCAUCCAGGACAUGGCCGUGCGGCAGCACCUGCUCACUAACCUGGUAGAGGUAGACGGGCGCUUCGUGUGGAGGGUGAACUUGGAUGCCCUGACCCAGCACCUAGACAAGAUCUUGGCUUUCCCACAGAGGCAGGAGUCCUACCUCGGGCCAACACUCUUUCUCCUUGGUGGAAACUCCCAGUUCGUGCAUCCCAGCCACCACCCUGAGAUUAUGCGGCUCUUCCCUCGGGCCCAGAUGCAGACGGUGCCGAACGCUGGCCACUGGAUCCACGCUGACCGCCCACAGGACUUCAUAGCUGCCAUCCGAGGCUUCCUGGUCUAAGAGUUGCUGGCAAGAAGAUGGCCGGGCGUGGUGGCUCAUGCCUGUAAUUCCAGCACUUUGGGAGGCUAAGGCGGGAGGAUGACUUGAGGCCAGGAGUUGGAGACCAGCCUGGCCAACAUGGUGAAACCCUGUCUCUACUAAAAAUACAAAAAUUAGCCUGGCGUGGUGGUGCACACCUGUAAUCCCAGCUACUCUGGAGGCUGAGGCAGGAGAAUCACUUGAACCCUGGAGGCAGAGGUUGCAAUGAGCCGAGAUCACACCACUACACUCCAGCCUAGGCAACAGAGCAAGACUCUGUCUCAAAAAAAACAAAACAAAAAGGAGGCACAAAACCCCAGGCUUCAAGUCUCUGCAGCCUGCUCCACAUUUGGGCACAGAAGGACUCAGACAGGCACUGUGUGGGCACGAGGUUUUACAGGGGUGGUCAGACCUCAGGCUUUAAUGAAUAAAGACACUACUCCCAAA